GCAUUUCCUGGUCUGGAGCCGGCUGAGCCACAGCAGGGUCGCCGCGGGGUCCCGGGGCCGUGCUCCCCUGCCCCUCCCGGGAGCGCGCGGGGCGGGGCGGGGCGGGGCGGGACCAGGCGGGCGAGCUGGGCCCUCGCCCCUCCCUCGGGCGGUCACCUGGGCACGGGCGCUGCAGGUGUCGGGGCCUCAACCUUGCGGAGCCGACAGCCAUCGAUCCUCGGGUGAGUGCGGGCGCAGGUGGAGGGCGCCCGGCGCUCUCGCCACCGGCGUCCCAGCCUCGGGGCGGCGAACGGUCCCCGCGCCGCUCCCAGCCUCCCUGGCCGGGCGUUCAGCGCGCCUGGGAGGGGAAGGAAUUUCCUUUGCAGGAACUCAGGGGCUGGGGGUUCUCUGCUACUUAAGAGAUCCAGGAGUGGAGCCCGGACGCCCGAGCCUUCCUGCUUCGGGAUGGGGAUUACCGCGGAGCCUUAGCAACUGGGGUGGCCUCGAGGUGGUGGCAGGGCCGCCCCCUGCAGUCCGGAGACGAACGCACGGACCGGGCCUCCGGAGGCAGGUUCGGCUGGAAGGAACCGCUCUCGCUUCGUCCUACACUUGCGCAAAUGUCUCCGGCUUGCUCCACUUAUCGGGCUCACCAAAUACAGCUGCAGUAUGAAUUCCAUCUUCUACACAACAGUAAACCAGAAUGUUCAUGUUCACAGCGUUCAUCUCCCAUCCUGUUGUCUAACGCACAUGGUUUUUUUAAACUUUUCUAAGAUUGCAUGAGAUUCUGCAACACAACUGAUUAUAAAAACACUUGAAGUUUUUACCUUUUUUUUUACUUUCCAACUCUCGUGAAUGUACAGAGGACUUUCCAGAAGCUACAUGAUGUGUGAUAUUUCAGCUGAUGAAAUGUAGAUGUAUAGGUAAUCGGUCAGAGUGGUGGGAGAAACUGUUGGGAAAGGAGCAGGCCUUCUGAAAGGUCGGAAGGCUUCAGGGGAGAAUAAGCUGAACGCAGCUGUUCUCUGACCUUGAGGCAGAGGGCAAGGAGUAGGUACAAGGACGUGUAGGAGAAUUUAUCUUAAAUAGGCUUGUUCACUUGUGUUGUCCAGAAACGACUUUUGAUCAUCAGCGCGCAUGACUGCUCCCUGAAAGGAAGAACAAUAAUGUUAAUUACCCGCAGACUGUGUUUGCUCCAGGCUUUCGGCAUUAUGUCUGUACUGAAUAAAAGCAAGCAGCUCCAGCUGUUCGAGGCUGCUCUCUUCUUCAGCCAUUAGUGCCGGGCAGCCCACUAGCUGCUGUUACACUGCAUAUCUGUGUCUGAGUACUCCUUUCUUCAGUUGCUUGGCCAGGGUCUGUGGGACAGACCCAGCAGCUGGUGCCCUGUGUGAGGAACGCUGCAAUGGAUCGCGACGGAACCCUCGAAAACGAAGGUGAAGAGACUGCGCAAGCUUACUCACAUAGCAUAUUGGUAUAUCAAAAUGAAAUGCAAGGAACCAAAAAUAACAUAAUUGAAGGCAGUAAAAGUGAAAUUAAAUAGGAAGAUCAUCAGUCAAGGAAGACCCACUGGAGAGGACAGAAAAUGAAGCAGUGUUUUAUCAUGUGUAUUUCAGCAGGUCUUCUUGAAAUUUAACUAAAAAUAUGACUGCUCUCUCUUCAGAGAACUGCUCUUUUCAGUACCAGUUACGUCAAACAAACCAGCCCCUAGAUGUUAACUAUCUGCUAUUCUUGAUCAUACUUGGGAAAAUAUUAUUAAAUAUCCUUACACUAGGAAUGAGAAGAAAAAACACCUGUCAAAAUUUUAUGGAAUAUUUUUGCAUUUCACUAGCAUUCGUUGAUCUUUUACUUUUGGUAAACAUUUCCAUUAUAUUGUAUUUCAGGGAUUUUGUACUUUUAAGCAUUAGGUUCACUAAAUACCACAUCUGCCUAUUUACUCAAAUUAUUUCCUUUACUUAUGGCUUUUUGCAUUAUCCAGUUUUCCUGACAGCUUGUAUAGAUUAUUGCCUGAAUUUCUCUAAAACAACCAAGCUUUCAUUUAAGUGUCAAAAAUUAUUUUAUUUCUUUACAGUAAUUUUAAUUUGGAUUUCAGUCCUUGCUUAUGUUUUGGGAGACCCAGCCAUCUACCAAAGCCUGAAGGCACAGAAUGCUUAUUCUCGUCACUGUCCUUUCUAUGUCAGCAUUCAGAGUUACUGGCUGUCAUUUUUCAUGGUGAUGAUUUUAUUUGUAGCUUUCAUAACCUGUUGGGAAGAAGUUACUACUUUGGUACAGGCUAUCAGGAUAACUUCCUAUAUGAAUGAAACUAUCUUAUAUUUUCCUUUUUCAUCCCACUCCAGUUAUACUGUGAGAUCUAAAAAAAUAUUCUUAUCCAAGCUCAUUGUCUGUUUUCUCAGUACCUGGUUACCAUUUGUACUACUUCAGGUAAUCAUUGUUUUACUUAAAGUUCAGAUUCCAGCAUAUAUUGAGAUGAAUAUUCCCUGGUUAUACUUUGUCAAUAGUUUUCUCAUUGCUACAGUGUAUUGGUUUAAUUGUCACAAGCUUAAUUUAAAAGACAUUGGAUUACCUUUGGAUCCAUUUGUCAACUGGAAGUGCUGCUUCAUUCCACUUACAAUUCCUAAUCUUGAGCAAAUUGAAAAGCCUAUAUCAAUAAUGAUUUGUUAAUAUUAUUAAUUAAAAGUUACAGCUGUCAUAAGAUCAUAAUUUUAUGAACAGAAAGAACUCAGGACAUAUUAAAAAAUAAACUGAACUAAAACAACUUUUGCCCCCUGACUGAUAGCAUUUCAGAAUGUGUCUUUUGAAGGGCUAUGAUACCAGUUAUUAAAUAGUGUUUUAUUUUAAAAACAAAAUAAUUCCAAGAAGUUUUUAUAGUUAUUCAGGGACACUAUAUUACAAAUAUUACUUUGUUAUUAACACAAAAAGUGAUAAGAGUUAACAUUUGGCUAUACUGAUGUUUGUGUUACUCAAAAAAACUACUGGAUGCAAACUGUUAUGUAAAUCUGAGAUUUCACUGACAACUUUAAGAUAUCAACCUAAACAUUUUUAUUAAAUGUUCAAAUGAAAGCAA